GACUCGAGUAACAUGGCCGCUGUCUCGUGAGUCCCGCUAGUGCCGGGCGGGAGUUGUUAAGCGGCCAGGGUCAGGUGUGCUGGAGCGGGGUCCGGGCCCGGGUUCCAGGGCGAGGCGGCGGAGCGUGGCAGGCAAGCCUAGAGCGGCGUGGUCCAUGCGCCGGCGCCGGGGGCAGAGCGGAGCCGCAGACUCCCCUGGCCCCGGCGCGGCCCCGGCAGCCGCGGGCUAAGGAGUCGCGAGGUUCCCCCAGCUGCCACCAUGAACCCCGAGAAGGAUUUCGCGCCGCUCACGCCUAACAUCGUGCGCGCCCUCAAUGACAAGCUGUACGAAAAGCGGAAGGUGGCAGCGCUGGAGAUCGAGAAGCUGGUCCGGGAGUUCGUGGCCCAGAACAAUACCGUGCAAAUCAAGCAUGUGAUCCAGACCCUGUCCCAGGAGUUUGCCCUGUCUCAGCACCCCCACAGCCGGAAAGGGGGCCUCAUCGGCCUGGCCGCCUGCUCCAUCGCACUGGGCAAGGACUCAGGGCUCUACCUGAAGGAGCUGAUCGAGCCAGUGCUGACCUGCUUCAAUGAUGCAGACAGCAGGCUGCGCUACUAUGCCUGCGAGGCCCUCUACAACAUCGUCAAGGUGGCCCGGGGCGCUGUGCUGCCCCACUUCAACGUGCUCUUUGACGGGCUGAGCAAGCUGGCAGCCGACCCAGACCCCAAUGUGAAAAGCGGAUCUGAGCUCCUAGACCGCCUUUUAAAGGACAUUGUGACUGAGAGCAACAAGUUUGACCUGGUGAGCUUCAUCCCCUUGUUGCGAGAGAGGAUUUACUCCAACAACCAGUAUGCCCGGCAGUUCAUCAUCUCCUGGAUCCUGGUUCUGGAGUCGGUGCCAGACAUUAACCUGCUGGAUUACCUGCCGGAGAUCCUGGAUGGACUCUUCCAGAUCCUGGGUGACAAUGGCAAAGAGAUUCGCAAAAUGUGUGAGGUUGUUCUUGGAGAAUUCUUAAAAGAAAUUAAGAAGAACCCCUCCAGUGUGAAGUUUGCUGAGAUGGCCAACAUCCUGGUGAUCCACUGCCAGACAACAGAUGACCUCAUCCAGCUGACAGCCAUGUGCUGGAUGCGGGAGUUCAUCCAGCUGGCGGGCCGCGUCAUGCUGCCUUACUCCUCCGGGAUCCUGACUGCUGUCUUGCCCUGCUUGGCCUACGAUGACCGCAAGAAAAGCAUCAAAGAAGUGGCCAACGUGUGCAACCAGAGCCUGAUGAAGCUGGUCACCCCCGAGGACGACGAGCUGGAUGAGCUGAGACCUGGGCAGAGGCAGGCAGAGCCCACCCCUGACGAUGCCCUGCCAAAGCAGGAGGGCACAGCCAGUGGAGGUCCAGAUGGUUCCUGUGACUCCAGCUUCAGUAGCGGCAUCAGUGUCUUCACUGCAGCCAGCACUGAAAGAGCCCCAGUGACCCUUCACCUCGACGGGAUCGUGCAGGUCCUAAACUGCCACCUCAGUGACACGGCCAUUGGGAUGAUGACCAGGAUUGCAGUUCUCAAGUGGCUCUACCACCUCUACAUCAAAACUCCUCGGAAGAUGUUCCGGCACACGGACAGCCUCUUUCCCAUCCUACUGCAGACGUUAUCGGAUGAAUCGGAUGAGGUGAUCCUGAAGGACCUGGAGGUGCUGGCAGAAAUCGCUUCCUCCCCCGCAGGCCAGACGGAUGACCCAGGCCCCCUCGAUGGCCCUGACCUCCAGGCCAGCCACUCAGAGCUCCAGGUGCCCACCCCUGGCAGAGCCGGCCUACUGAACACCUCUGGUACCAAAGGCUUAGAAUGUUCUCCUUCAACUCCCACCAUGAAUUCUUACUUUUAUAAGUUCAUGAUCAACCUUCUCAAGAGAUUCAGCAGCGAACGGAAGCUCCUGGAGGUCAGAGGCCCUUUCAUCAUCAGAAGGGGUGUGACCUGCCCCGGCCCCAGUCUUGAGCUCCAGCUCCAGACCACAUGGGCGGAUAGCCCCAACAUGGGGCCAUCGGGGCCUCCUCAGUACCCCAGGAGAGCAUUUGCUUCCACCUGAUUGUGGCACUUGUGUCUCCGUUUCACCAUCCACCUCGUCAUCAGUAAACCUGUGUCCUCAGAUGGGCCCUUCUGCCCCCAGGCUUGCUAUUUGCAUAUCCACUCCUUUCCCUCUGAAGGAAGAACAGUCAUCCAAACUUGACAACUCCCAGCCCUUCCCACUGCUUCAGAGAGAAAGGUGCCUUGGAAGCUCCACCGUGCCCGAGACACUGUCUUGUUUUCAGCUUGGUCUUGCCGUCUCCCCGGGAAGCGUUCUCCCUUUCUUACCACAUAACACAUGCUUCAGCACCCCAGAUGUGUCUUCUUUCCUCGUCCUGAUCAAAGCGGUGUGGCAGCCUCAACUCCCUCCAGGCUCGAUGCCUGGAUGUCUUUGGUGACUGUAAAUUUAAAGAACGUACUAUUUGAAAGUGCACAAAUCAUGAGUGUGCUCUUGUAAAUUUUCACUAACUGUGACACCAGGGAAUGAGCCCUCUGAUCAAGAAAUAGAACAUUUCCAGCACCAGAGAGGUCACUUUCACGUCUCCUGCAAGUGACAGCCCCUCCCCGCCUCCCUCAAGUACUGACUCCAACACAAGAGGUUCAUCUUGCCUGGUUUUGAGCUUCAUAUAAAUGGAACCGUACAGCUGGUGCUCUUUUCACAAAGCCUGGCUUCUUUGGAUCCACAUUGGGUUUGUGAGAUUCGUCUGUGUUGGAUGUCACAGUAGUUCACAUUUCCAUGGAAUAUUCUGUAUGACGAUACCGUGAUUUAUUUAUCUCUUCUAGUAUUGAUGGGCAUGGGGGUUAUUUUCGGUUUGACACUAUUAUGGAUAAUGCUUUCUUAUGUGCCUUUUGAUAACCAUAUAGACACAUUUCUAUUAGGUAUAUACCUAGGAAUUGCUGGAUUGGCAAGCAGACAUACCAUGGGCUUAGGGAGGUACUGUCCAAAGUGCUUGUGCCAGCUUCCACUCCCGUCAGCAUUGUGGGAGAGUUCCAGUUGCUCCACGUCCUCACCAACACUUGGUAUCAUCAGUCUUUGAUUUUAGCCAUUCUGAUUAGGGGUACAGUAGUAUCAUCUUGUGGUUUUAAUAUGCAUUUCCCUAAAGACUAAUGAAGUUGAACAACUUUUCAUAGCUUAGUGGCCUUUUGGAUAUCCUCUUUUGUGACGAGUCUGUUCAAGUCUCAUUUUCCCAUUGAGUUUUUGGUGUUUUUCUUAUUGAUUUGUGGAAGUCCUUUGUAUAUUCUGAAUCUGAGUCUUUCUCAGUUGUAUAUACUGUCAUUAUCUUCUCCUACUCUGUGGCAUGCCUUAUCACUCCCUUAAUGAUGUCCUUUGAUGAACAGACAUACUUUAUUUUUAAUCUAGUCCAGGUAAUCAAUUUUUCUUUACAGUUAGCAUUUUUUUUGUUUUGUGAUGCUUUUUCGGGGAAUUAGGAGCUCAUGGAAACAUAUCCAUGAAGCCGCCUGUUUCUGAGUGAUGAUUGUUCCGCAUUCCCAGUAAGCGGAUGCUGAGCAUGAUCCACCUGGAAUCGAGAGGUGUUUUUUCUUAAUUCUUGACAGGGUCUUGGAAACCAGCUAGUCCAGCCUGUUUGUGCUUUGUAAAAGCAAAGUUUCCUAGCCAUCCUGCCAGCCCUCCCGACCUGCCAGAAUCCAAGGGGCUUCUGCGGCAGCCAGGCCAGCGGUGGUCUGCAGCCUGGAGCUGGGAACCACUAAUCUUACUGUAUUGGGCAGCACCCUUUGGGUGGCAUGUGGUAGGAACCCAGGUCAAAGGCACCAAAAUGAGCAAAGGAACUUCACUGGCCUCUGUAUCCAGACCAAGACCAGGGUCAGCAAGAUCUCUGCAGUCUUUGUUUGAGGUCAGCCAUGCUGUUUUGGUCUCUUCCAAGUGGCAGAGACACGGCCACCACAUCGCCUGGGCAUUGCAUCCCAGCCAGUUAUGAUCCAGAGGGAAGCUCUGAUUGGCCCAGACAGGGCCAGUGGCAGGGAGGUGGGGCUGAGGGGUGCUGUGAGUGGCAGCCCUAACAGAACCCCACGUGGAGUUGGGGAGCAACAGCACACCUAAGGAAAGGGGUCACUCUUCCCACGAGAUGCUGAGCCAGGAGAACCACAGGGGCUGGCCAUGUGGCUGCCUUCCCAAGCACAGUUUUCUUUGUUUUUUUGUUUUUUUUUUUUUUAAAAAGGAGUCUCAUUCUGUCACCCAGACUGGAGUGCAGUGGCGCAAUCUUGUCUCACUGCAAGCUCUGCCUCCUGGGUUCAUGCCAUUCUCCCCUGCCUCAGCCUCCCGAGUAGUUGGGACUACAGGCGCCCACGACCACACCCGGCUAAUUUUUUGUAUUUUUAGUAGAGACGGGGUUUCACCAUGUUAGCCAGGAUGGUCUCAAUCUCCUGACCCCGUGAUCCGCCCGCCUUGGCCUCCCAAAGUGCUGGGAUUACAGGCGUGAGCCACCGCACCCAGCCCCAAGCACAGUUUUCUUAAAAGAGAAAUGCAGACGGGGAUCAUCACUAUCUCCUCCUAAUCCCUGUGAGACUGAGUGACGAAGCAUAUGGAAAGUGCUUAGGAGACAGCCUGGCACCUAGUAACUUGUGCACUCAGUACCAGAAGCAACUAGUAGAUAACUGUGAGGAGCCGAGGAGCUCCCGGGGUGGGCAGUGGCUGGUCACAGAGCCAGGCUUGGCCCAACUGCUCCCUCGGGCUCAGCUCCUGGAACGCAGGUGUUCUGGGGUUGACUCACUUUCUCCUGUUUCUAGAGAAGAGUAAGAGAGAAAGUUAUAGAGUCAUUCAGAUGAAUACUCAAGGCCGGGCGCGGUGGCUCAUGCCAGUAAUCCCACACUUUGGGAGGCCAAGGCAGGCAGAUCACUUGAGCCCAGGAGUGCAAGACCAGCCUGAGCAACAUGGUGAAACCCUUGCCGCCCUACAAAAAAAGAGAAAUAUAAUUAACUGAGCAUGGUGGCAUGCGCCUGUGGUCUCAGCUACUCAGGAGGCUGAGGCGAGAGGGAGGCUUAAGCAGAGGUUGCAGUGAGCUGAGAUCGUGCCACUGCACUCCAGCCUGGGUGACAGAGUGAGACCCUGUCUCAAAAAAAAGAAAAAGAAAAAAAUGAAUACUCAAACCCCAGCACUCUCCCGUCUUCUGUCCCCCAACCCACCCAGCAACUAGCUCUUGUCCAGUUCUGUGCAGUCAGGACUCUGGACGGCACAUGGCAGAAAACCAAUUCUCACCCUUACAGGAAGAAAAACAAAGGUAUCAAUACUAUUCAGUGUGCCGAUCUAUAUCCGGAAAAUACAUUCUAUACUUUUUUAAAAAAAGAAAAAUAAAGGUAGUGUGCAGGCAGAGGCGAGGAUGGGCUCAUUUAAAACUAGAAGUUCAAGGCUCAGGCCACCUCCUGUCCUCAAGUCCUCCUCUCCCCCGCCACAGCUGGCUCUUCCUCCUCCAUCUGCCCCAUUAGUGGACAGGCCACCCGCUUUGUGGCCAGGUGGCUCGCUCCGGCCCUCUCGGCACCCCAGCCUUCAGCACCUGUCCUGGGCUCAUGUCCCAUGGGACCCAUCAGUGUGGCCAGAGUGCGCUGGUGCUGAUUGCCCUGAAAAGGGUCGGGUGCCCACCCUCAGACACAGGAGCAGGUGUCAUGGGCCGUCAUGGUUCUGGAACCAGAAUCCAAGGCCAUGGACAUCAGGAGGCAGAGCCAACAAUGGUGUGGACCUGGUGGUCUGGGUUUAAAUGCUCACAGAGGAGGAGUGUGAAGUAGGCCCUACCAAGGGCCACCAUGGGGGUAACUGAAGGAGUGACUUUUUCACCUCCAAGCAGCCAACUCCUUCCUUCCUGCAGGAAAGUGGGAGGGUGAAGCUGUAUAUGUGACCCAGUGACCCUCCAGAUCCACAGUGGGAGCAGGCAGUGAGGAGGUGGUGGCCAGGUAUGGCCUCCAGCUGAUUCCUCCUUUGUGGCCUCCUUCCGCCAACAGCACUAUUUCUGGAAGCAUCCAUGCAGGCAGAGCGGAUGGGUCUUCUACCCUUUGUCGCGUGUGGAAUUGGGACGCAGGCCCAGCACCUCAUACCAGGGCCCGCUUGGGGCCCUGUCUCCAUACAUGUGACCCAGGCCUGGGUAGCCGCAGGGCCAAAACUGAUCAGAGUCCCAGAGAGUCUCAGUCAGGGAGAAGCCAGGAGGGACCUUAUGGGCCAGUUGGGUUCUUUCAUACAGAAAGAAACUGAGGCUUUGAUUUCUCCUGUAAAUAUUUACUGCCUGCUGCCUUUGUACGGAGGAGGGCCUGGGCCAGGCCAACAUGGGCCCAGCCUCCACAGACCGGGGAGAAGGUAUUUCAGGGAGAUGGGAACAUCUUAUAGGGGCUGGACAAGAGCACUGGGGAGUUCAUAAGGAGAGAGCUCCCUGGCUGGGGAACAGGGGUCAAAGAUUCACUCACUCCACACAGAGGGGCAUUCCGCAAAUAUUCCUGAGUGCCUGGGAUGUGCCAGGCCCCAUGCCAGCUGUGGCAUGGCUCACGCCUCCCCCGGGGCUGCAGCCUCAUGGGAGGGGCCCACAGGGACAAGUAACAAAGAAACAGGUGACCUGGUCUUGUGAUCCAUGCUCUGAAGAAAACACUGGGGGAGGUGGAGGGGGGUCCUCAGGUCAGGCCUGUGAGAAGGGGGGUGCCCCACAGCGUCAGUAGAGCCAGGAAGCUGUGACCUGGAUCUGAGGUUUUCUGAAAGCAUAAAAGUGCCCUAGUUUUCCCCUCUCCUCAGGCUCCGCUGAAGCUAUGCCAAGAAUUGGCUUUUAAAGGCUGCCUGAAAUGUGGUUUGGAGCCAAAAAUCUAUAGAGCCAGCGCAUUUGUGACCUUGUUGAAAAUGCUUACUGAGGAAAAACAAGGGGGUGGGAUUUGGGAUUUUCUUUUUCCCUUGUAAAAUUUAAAAAUACAUGUAUCUGUCUGGUCUGUCCCCACCCCUUCUCUAUCCCGCCUGCAGGCCCUCACCUUGGCCCGACAGCCCCGACUCCACCGCAUACGCGUCUUCCAUUAGCCCACACCUCCCCCAUUCCCAAUCCCUGGCCAUCUCCCAUGCAUCAGUAAUGAAAAAUACCAAGUGGGUAAAAAUAAGGAGCCCGGUUAUAGCCCUGGAAAUUAGGCCACAGCUGUCAGGCCGGGCAAGAGCGCUCGCCUCUCUGAGAAUGGAACCGCCGGGAGCAAGAGCUCGGCCCCCUCCCUGCAAGGGUAGAUCAGAGUUUCACCCAGGGGGCGGCAGGGCGCUGCUGCUGUGCUGGGCAGGCAGGGGAGCCAGGAAGCGCCAUGUAUCACUGAGCAACCCUGUCCUGGGUGUCCGUCAGUGCCUGGCACAGUGCCCACCAGUGGGAACACCGCAGUGGGCAGAGCUAGUCCCUGCCCGCCAGGGUUAGUCACGAUUGCAAGCAUAGCAUCGCACAGUGGUGAUCCUUGGUGAAACAGAUGUGGGGGAGGGGGUGCCCAGCCUGUUGGGGGAGUCUGGGAAAGCUUCUGAAACGUGACAUCUAAGCUGAGCCAGGAAAGAUGAGUAGGAACUGGUCGGGGAAGGAGUGGGGGAGGUGUUUCUGACACAGCAAGCAGUCUGCUCAGAAGCCCAGAGACCAGUCCCCACACCCUCUGGGCAACCUGGAGUGUGGCUGGGAGGCCCCUGGUGGCCUUACCUCUGAGGUACCCUGUGAGCCAGUGGAGGGCUGAAGCAGGUUCAGAAAACCUCCUACCGCUGUGUGAGGGUGCCCAAGUCCCUGAGAGGAGCCUUCAGAUAGGCAGUGGGCAUGUGCCAGGCUGUGCCUGAGGUGGCUGGCUCACAGAGCUUCCAGUGGGACGGAGGGAAGUGGGGCCCAGGGCUCGCCAGUGGGGGCAGGUGGUGAGACCCUCACUUGUUCACCAUGACAGCUGUGGCCCUACACACUCUCCUCUGCCAUUAGUCUCGUGAAACACCGCAGGCUAGUUAGGAAGCCGGCUCAGGAAGCUGGCUUGACCAGGGUUCUUGCUGCUGUGUCAUUCUGGAAGGUUCAGUGCUGCUAGGACAGGCAGUUUAAGCAGAUAAUCUGGACUAAGUUUAAAACCAUCUCGACACCGCAGACAUCCCUGCCAUGGACUUGUUUGGCUCUUCAGGGUACGCUGGCUUCAGUCAGCUAAUGCCAGGUGCCUGUGAACUCGGCCAGCUUUCCUUGUCCACUCAUUUUUCCUGAGAAGAGUCAGCUUUUUCCUUCCUCUCCCAUGAGCUGAGCCCCUCCUUCCAGCCCUUUUCCUGAAGAAGACCCCCACCUACCUCUGUUGGAAGCCCCCUGCCCCCACAGUUGACAGGUUCCUGGAGUCACCUCCAUUCCUGCCCUUGAAGCGUGAGCGGCUGUCCCGGUCCAGUUCCUUCUGCUUCUCCUGGGCCCCCCAGUAGCAUAGUAAUUGGUUUCUCAGAUCUUCAGCUGCGUGCCCCGUCUGUGAAUAUUUCCCAGUCCCUGACCCUCGCGGGAAGACCCAUCUAUGAUCUUACCCCUGUGGGGAUCCUCAGGGGAGAGAGAUGAUGGAGAGAUGACUGAUCCUUCCAGUCUCUUCUCUCAUUCCUGCCAGUGAUGCCUAAAAUAGAGAGCAAAAUUGCCACCUCUCUGCCCCAGCCCCCUCCCCGACCCCCGCAGCCCAAGGUCGCAGGCCCCCAGGAUGGGCCCUGGGCCUGGUAAGCAAGCAGGCCACAGGAGAGGGGCGCUGGAGCAGCUGCCGAGUGCCCUGUUUCCAGCAGCUGCAGAGAUUUGUAUCUGCAGUUACCGCUCCUGGAGGGUCACAGCCUCCGUUUCAUUUUUGUGGUGUUUGAAGAAGAGUUCAAGCCUUUCUCCACGUAUACACAGGCCCACAGGCCCAGGUUCGGGCUUCCCACAGCCAGCUAAUGGGUUUCUAGGAGAGAAAAGAUAGCAAUCAAAUAUAUGCCCACAGGCUGGGCGUAGUGGCUCACGCCAGAAUCCCAGCACUUUAGUAGGCAGAGGUGGGUGGAUCACUUGAGCCCAGGAGUUCAAGACCAACCUGGGCAACAUGGCAAGACCCCAUCUCUACAAAAAAAAAAAAAAACAAAAACAAAGAUGCUCCUGAGCAGGAGAGUGGGGAGCCCAGGAGGCAAGUGCUCUGGGUUGAUAGAGGGUCCCAGAGGAGCAGACAUCUGACUCACAGUGGUGUGGCCUCUGGGGAAGGUGCCUCCCUAAGAUUUCAUCAUCUGUGUCUCCUCAAGCCUGCCCUCUUCCACGUCCAUUCCCCUGGCCAUUCUUGACUGGGCUCUUCCCUACCCCCAGGGGAAGGACGUCUGGAAAGGCAGCCCGAAACCCUUUGUACUUUAAUUGGAAGAAGGUGGGAGCCUGAGGCAAAAGUGAUUCAAACAGCACCCAGAAUGGUGGUCUUCAGGGCGGAACUGUGGUCAGCGUUUCCAUCCUCAGACCCUGCUCUAUGCUGGUGGCUGCAGCGCGCCCGUCAUAGCCAGGCUGUUCGCGCACGGUAGCUUUUUUGCUCUAAGUGGAGAUGGGGGCUUCGUCUCCAUUGAUAAGACUUUCCUCAUCUGCUGGCGAUUCUAUUUUAGGAGAAAGCCUCCCCCUGUAGUAGGCACUCCUGCCUCAAAGUGGAGCCAGGCCUUUUUUUUCGUGCUUGUAUUAUGCUAAUCACUCCUUGCAAGCAGGCAGACUUUGUAGGAGGUUUGCCUGGUUUUAGAUGAAACAUACGCCUUUGAAGCAAAGAGCCACCGUAGCUAAAAAUACCUUUUCCUGGCUGUUGAUCCUCUCAUUUGUAAAAUGCAUGUUUCCAUUGUUAAACCUGCAGCAGCCCCUCUAGAGAGGAAAGCUCCACUAUCGUGGCCAGGCUGGAGCACCCAUGCCCUGGGGAGGUAGCACCUUCCCCAGCCCUGCCCGUGGGCUCCGUCGCCAAGCCUCUCCAAGAAGGAGUCCAAGAGAAGCACACAGAGGAUUCUCAAUACUUUAUUUUCUGUUUAGAAAUAUUAAACCACAUACAAUAAAAACUGAAAUAAUGCAGAAUGGUAUAGCAGUAAAUGGGAAAGACCCCUGACCACCUGCCACCUCCUCCCUCAGAAGUAGCCUCUGGGUCUCAGCUUGGUGUGUUUCCUUCUGCAGCCCUUUCUGUGCAUUUAUCAGCAUGAGGCUCGGUCUGGUGCUGGUUUGGCAGCAGUGGUCUCUGGACUCGGAGAGCUCUGCAGCUUGCCCAGGUCCACCGCCUUCACUGUCUUUGUGCAGAACACAUCUCCCUCCGGAUCCUGAGCCCGGCUAGACACUGCCUCUACGCUCCCAGCCUGAGCCCAAUGGCUCAGGGUCACUGUCCCUCCCCACGGAGGCUGCCAUAUCCCAGUAUUAAAUCUGUCCACCCGCCUUUCUCUGUCGGUGGUUACCUCGUGUCUUUGCUCAGAGGGGCAGUGGCGUGAUCCUGGUGGGGAGUGGAGGGAGCAGGCCUCUUGCCCACCAGCGCAAGUUCUGCUAUAGGGCGCCUCGCCUGUAACCCAGAGCUAGGACUAAGACAUGUCCCCUCGGGUGACUUCCAAGGACGCCUCAUGUCUGGGGCCCUCUUAUUUCUCACGCGUUUAAUCCAGGGAAGAUUUCCUGGGCUGGCAGGGAACAUGUGGAUGAAAAGCCUAUUUCAUCCGUCUUAAAAUUCUCUGAAAAUGGCUGAUCACAAAAGGAAUUUUUUCAGCCUCCCGGGAGGGGGUGGGGGAGGGUACAAAUAGGAGAACCCCUCCCCUUCCAUUUGGCCGAGAAUAACUGAAGGAGCCCCCUCCCAGCCAUGCUGUGGCCCACCACUACGGCUGUGGCACCUCCAUCCUCCCAGUCCUUUGAGACUCUGAUCUUUUUACCGGCCUCUCAGAGGCCGCCGUGAGGCUGCUCUGAUAUUUGCUCUUUGUUACCACUGGUGAGUAUUCAUGUUUAACUUCUCGUCCUGUUUCCUGACACUUAUCUCAGUGCUCUUUAAGUGGGCACUUAUAAAGCCUAGAGAAAGCCAUCUCAGUUCAUAAAAUUUCACAAAACCCCUGGACUAAAGAUGUGAAGACAAGAAAGGCACUCAUGGCUCUAGCUCCUAAUCACAGCCAGAAAGGCAGGAAUGGCCCGUGCCCAGGGCAGCAGCUGUGAGCUGUGCUUCCUCUUGGGGUGCUGGGGCUAUGCAGGUGGGCCAGGCCACAUGGCUGUCAGGAGGCCAGGGAGAGUCCAAGCACAGGUCUUGCCCAAGAGCUGACCUCUUUAUCUUUCUGUUUGAACAGAGGAGGCCAGGGCUGUGCACAGCAGGCUCGGGACCGUGAAGGUAGAGACCAGCAGGGAAACAGUGAAAUGCCAAGCAGAAACGUAAACCAGGACCCAGACUCUGCACAGGUGGGGGUGGGGCCUCAAGAAGGCAAGUGUCAGGGCCUUCCGCCUAGAGCUCCAAGGCCGAGCCAGGCCCUGCUGCCACCCAUCCUCUCAGACUCCUGCCAGAGUCUCCUCCUUCCCUCAGGAGGGCAUGGCCAUGCCUGAAGCGAUCAGGCCUGGUGAGGCAGUUGCAGGCAGCAGGUCUCUGGCCGCCCCGGAAGCUUGUUGAGAGUACAGAUCGUGGACCUCCUGGAGGUGAGGCCCGCACGUGGUCCAUGCAUACAGCCAGGCUCUGGGGUUCCUCAGUUAGGGUAUUCCUGGCUUGAGGGACCCUCUUUGUUCUAGAGGGUAAAUGCGCAGCCUUCUGGGUGGAUGAGGACACUGAUGGGACAGGGGCUGGCGGCUCCCCGCUGAGGGACGUGGAGCUGAAGCCAUGCGCAUGGCGCCCAGGGCAGAGCACUCGAGGUGCCCCCAGAAACCAGAAUGGCAGCCCCUGGCCGGAACUCCUUCAGAGCGCAGGAGGUCCUUUGAAGGAAAGUUGCCACGGGAACACGAGAGACUAGUGAAUCACUGUAAUCACCCAGGGCCCAUGACCAGGAGGACAGCCCAUCUGGUUAAAUAAUUUGGGGGAGGGAAAUGUUGACACGGGGCUAUGGCCAUAUGAACACUGGGGCUGCUGGACCCAAGUUGGGUCCGUGGCUUCAAGGCCAGAGGGGCCGAGUGUGGGCCCUGCCGAGGCCUCCGUGUCUUGGUCCAGCACCGACGAGGCAGAAGGGGAGGCUCACCAUCUGUAAACUGUGGAAUACGCAGCAGCUGGAGUGCUCCCUGGCCUGGAACAAAGGGACUAGUUUGGGAAUCGUCGCCUGAAGUAAAGGAAAACAAACAGCUUGGUGAUCAGAACACGGGCAAGGGGCGUCGCCAGACAUUGUUGGGGCCGGAGUAGCUCUGGCCACCUUACUCGGGUCCCAGCACUGCUGUCCCUCACCCGCCUCAUUCCUCACAAGUCCCCCUGCGGUUUGCAGGGGAAAAUGGCAGAGAUGCAGGGAUGCCUUUCCAUUACCCGUCCCAAGACAGACUCAAUCUCCGAGGACCCUGUGUGAGGUCACAUGCCACAGGGUGAAGGGGUGUCUCUGCCCUGGGCAUACAAGCUGCAGGGAAUGGGUGGGAAGGGGAGCCAGCCAGGGAAGGGAGGUCUGUGUCCCUUGCAGAUGCCACAGAGCAUGGGAACAUGUUCAUGGGAACAUGAGUGCCAGGUCAGAAACCCAAGUUCUGGCCCCUCUGUGGCCCUGGCUGUGUGGCCUGGGACCAGUCCUUGGCUUCAGUUCCUUCCUGUCCCAUGCGGGUGGCAGGGGCGUGCAAGGGCAGGCAGGGCCAGGAAGCAGCGUGCCAGGCGGUGGCGGCCUCCUCGUGGGCAGGGCUGGCCUCCACGGGGGCAGCUGAGCACAUCCUCAGGAGGAAAUCCUGCUUAGAGGGUUCAAGCCCAGAGGGCUUCAAAGGGAGAGAAAGGUUACAGCUGCAGUUCUCCAGCAGAGCCCAGGAGGCCCCAGGGCAGGUAGGGUUCAGGGAUGCCAUUUCCCUGGCCAUUUCCCUGGCAGUGUCAGCCAGGGAAUGUAUCAGCCAGUUCAGAGCACCAGCCUUGGCCAUGUCUCCCUGGGCACCAGGAAUCUUUAUAUUAAAAUCUCCCCAGCCUGGACCUCAGGCAGUAGCUGGCCUGACUCCCAUACUCAGGAGCUGCUGCUCCCAACUGGUUUCCGGGAACCUGCUGUUGGAGUCAGCCCCGUGGACUUUCUCCGCUGGGUCAGAGUUUGGGUCCAGGCUACAGAACUAUGGCUGCAGUUUCAAGGCCCUGCUUCCCUCUCGUACCCUUGGAGACAAACCAUUGCCCUAGGAGGGUAGAACUAAGUGUGGAUCACAGGCCAACACCAUCCCAGCCAGGUGUGGUCAGUGCCAUCCACCCACAGAGGUGGCUCCAGCGGGAGAGUGGGGUAAAAGGAGCUGGCUACAGAUAUGCUGCCCCGGAGCCACAGGAAGCUUCUGGAGAAACUCGCUCCAGUCCACACCAGAAGGCCCCAGUGAUCUCUGCAGCUCAGGAGGUCCAAACUGUCUUCCCGGAAAAGUGUGUCUAAGGCUCUGUGCUGUGUAGGCCCUGGAGCUUGUUGGGGGACAAAGGGGUGGGUGGGCAGCAGUGAGUACUUGGUGCUGGGGUUAGGCUGACCAAGGGGGUCUUUGGCAAGGCCUCUCAUCUGUGCCGCACAUGGCAUUCUCUGCUAGAAAGGGCUCUGGGCUGAAAUCACAAGUGGCCCAUGCUGAGGAGUUGAAUGUACACGAUGUUCCUAAUGUACUGUCAUUUGUGGCCAGGAUUAGGAAGGAAAUGGUGAUUCCAGCUUGGAGGAAAUCCCUGUGGCAAGAGAGGGCAGGAGCCCAGCAGGGACCCAAGGGCUUGGGCACUUCUCAGCACUUCUUGGAGUUGAUUAUCAUGGAGACAACAGGAUUUCCUUUAGUGACCAGUCCCUUUGUUUUCAUUUGCACUGAGGAUUCAGCAUGCAAGAAGGUCCCUGCGGCCGUGCCAAGGCUUCAUGGCCGGGGGACAAUGGUCUCCAGGCAGGGGCCAGACCGGCCGCACUCUUGCCCCUCCUCCCCGCACCCAGCUGUCUCCUCACCCCGGCCUUGCCCUCCUCACACUGCGUUUUUCUCCAACACCAAGACACUAUCUCAGCAGAUACCCCAUCGGUCCUUCCUGCUAUCUCAGCUUCAGAGCCUCCAGCACAGGGUUACACGCCUGUCCCCAGCCCUCGCCAUCUGACCUGCAUCCAGCCGUAUUCUGGGGUGUGUCUAUGUGGGAUAGAAGGCGCAGCCUCUUUUCUAAGACACAAACGCAGACCUCAUUGUGAGUCAAACACCUGCUGAGUUCCCUCACAGGGACUCCUUGCAGAAUGCGAAAUGCUUCCGCCAGAGCCAGACACCCGCCAAGAACCCUGAUAACACAGUUCAGAACCCACCUGACUCUGAAGCCCCUUGGCCUGCAGUUCCAUGUGCAUGCCCAGCCCCACGGCCAAAGUAACCCAGGCCACCUUGUCCCUUCCUGGAAGUUAAUUUUCUGUCCUACAAGCAUUCAUCUCCCCCAUUGCCUGUAGGGGCCCAGCCCUAGGCCUUGUGGUGUAAGCUGAAAAGGAACCAGGGCUCAGGGAGGGCCCAGGGGCCAAGUACCACCUUAGGAAGGAAAUUGGUGGGAACUAGCAGCAGGUGAGGCAGGAGACAGGGGAGGGCUGUCCUGGGAAAGAACAGGGGGCUUGAGUACCUGUGAAUGGACACAGGGGACGGGGUGGUCAGACUGAAAAGACACAUGGAAAAUAAGGCCAAGGCAGGUGCGGUGGCUCACGCCUGUCAUCCCAGCACUUUGGAAGGCCAAAGCGGCAGAUCACCUGAGGUCAGGAGUUCAAGACCAGCCUGGCCAACAUGGUGAAACCCAGUCUCUACUAAAAAUACAAAAAUUAGCCAGGUGUGGUGACGGGCGCCUGUAAUCCCAGCUACUCAGGAGGCUGAGGCAGGAGAAUCACUUGAACCCAGGAGGCAGAGGUUGCAGCGAGCCAAGAUCACACCACUGCACUGGAUGACAGAGCGAGACUCCAUCUUGAAAAAAAAAAAAAGAAAAAAGGCCAAGCCAGCCCGAUGGGCCAAGGUAGAAGAUGACUUCCAUUCUGAGGAGAAGGCAGAGCCCCUCCCGUGGCAGCAAGGGUCAUCUGACUCCACCCUGGGCAGUUCAGAAAGCGGGAGUCAACUUGCUCUCUAGAGCAAGCCCCAAACUUAGGGUGAGGGACCUGCUAAUCCUGGGGGGCUGAGGCUUCAGCUGCCUCUGUGAGACUGUUUCGUUUUCUGUGGCAGCUCCCACCCAGAUGAGACCUUCUAUGGAGGUCUCUAGAUGAGCCCAGCACAGGUGUCUGGGACCUCCCAGAGCCCGAUGGCACCUCCUCUUGCACAGAGGGACAGAUGGCUAAGAGGACUGAAGGCCUCUUCCUGUGCCCCUCCUCCCUCCAUCCCCUUUCCACCAGCUCCCUACAAAGCCCAGAAAAACAAGUUCCGCAUCCUCCUCCUCCUCCCACCCCACUCCCUGCAAGAAACUUUUAAGUGUACCAGACACAUCGACUGCAUUAAACAACGAUGAAUUUUUAAGGCAUGAGUUGGCAGGGUUACCAUGGCUGCCUUUGCCCUGAGGGGCACACUGCCGAGGAUUGAUUGAAAUAAAUAAAACAGAUUUACAGUUUUCA